UGAUCAGAAGCCUGGGGAAUUUGCAGCGGAGCUGCUAUUCCUGGGAUGUUGUCCAGGUCUGGAGUCUGUGCCUUACACCCACUCUGACCCUGCCUCAGCCUAGAGUAAUAGAGUGCAGGGAUCACAAAGUCAAAUGCCUGCAGGAGCCAGGUGUAUAAGCUGGAGGAGUGAAGCAGGCUGAGUGGGACAAUGGUCACUGGGCCAGCCCAUGCCUGGUUUAGAUGGGACAGCCGUUCUCAAGUUCUAGAUGAUGGUUGCUGUGAGGUUGUGAUGGUUCAGCAUUGCCACAUCUUAUGAUUUUACAAGAAAAACUAGAAAUCUAGAUUUUAGUGUGAGGAAUCCUAAUUUGCAAAUGUUAGCAACUAAUCAGACACAUACAGACAGUGUAGGCCAAGCAAAUCAUGUCUCCAGCUGAAAUUCAGCCCAUGGGUCAUUAGUUUGUGACCUUGGGCAUAAUGCUACCAACAUCCAAUGGGAAGAGAGUGUCAAGGUUGAGAAGGGAUGAGGAAACUGAAGGUGUUAUGAUCACUUUGGCCUCCAUGGGGUUGCAUCCAAUGGUCUUCCCCAUUGAGUGGGGAUGAGGAAUCUGAAGGUAGUAACUGAUUCCUAGCUCCAGGAUGAUGCCAGUGGACAAAAUGAGAGUGAAACUCACCUUCUUAACUAUAAGCAAUGGAGAGUCCCUGAUGUGUAACACAGAGCCCCCAAAGGAAGGGGGAGACGUCCUCUCAAGUUUGAGAGGGGAUGGAGAAGACCAUUAGAUGCAACCCUAUGGAGGCCAAAGUGAUCAUAAGCCAUUUCAUAGUGGCUUAGGAGAGAUGGCAAGGAAGAAGAGGUUACUCUUGACAAGUUUGGCAGUGAAGGGAAGCUGGAGGGGAUAUUGGGGAGAAACAUGUCAUUCCCCUAUCCCUAAUCCUCAUUCAUUGGCAGACCUGUAUAUCUCUGUACAUAGUAAGGAGGGAAAUAUUUGGAAAUACUGUAUUGAAGAAGAGAGGAUAGAAUCAAGAACACAGCUGGUGGAGUGUGUAUUCUCUUGAGUAGAACUAUGAAGAAUGAUGAGGGUAGAUCCAGAGAUGUUUUGAGAUACCUUGAAGUUUUGGAGAUAUCACAUUGGCUUCAUAUUCAUAAAAUAGAAGGGUAUCUGUGCAGAUCAAGUGAAAGUUUUCAGCUAUCAUCGCUACCAAAGAGUAGAAAUGAAUGAAAAUGCACUGGUGGAGCUAAAGAAGCUAUUCGAUGCCAAAUCUGAGCACCUCCACCAGACCCUGGCCCUUCAUUCUUAUACUUCUGUGCUCUCAAGAUUGCAAGUGGAGUCUUACAUCUAUGCAUUGCUCAGUAGUUCAGCUGUUCUGAGAUCUUCAGCAAUUCACCAGCAAGGCCGAGCGUCUAAGCAGACAGAAAGCAUUCCCUCUGAUCUGUGUCAACUAAAGGAAUGCAUUAGUGUCUUAUUCAUGUUCACCAGGAGAGUUAAUGAAGAUACUCAGUUUCAUGAUGAUAUUCUUCUCUGGCUGCAGAAAUUGGUAUCCGUGCUACAAAGAGUUGGCUGUCCUGGAGAUCACCUCUUCCUUCUAAACCAUAUUCUUCGAUGCCCCGCUGGUGUUAGUAAAUGGGCUGUUCCUUUUAUCCAGAUCAAAGUGUUGCAUAACCCAUCAGGGGUCUUUCAUUUUAUGCAAUCCCUUGCCCUGCUGAUGUCUCCUGUCAAAAAUCGAGCUGAGUUUAUGUGCCACAUGAAGCCCAGCGAGCGGAAGCCAUCCUCCUCAGGGCCUGGGUCUGGGACUUGGACGCUAGUAGACGAAGGAGGAGAAGAGGAUGAAGACCCUGAGACCAGUUGGAUUCUCCUUAAUGAAGAUGAUUUGGUUACCAUUUUAGCACAGUUCCCCUUUCAUGAACUCUUUCAGCAUCUUCUUGGGUUUAAAGCAAAAGGUGAUUAUUUACCUGAAACAACAAGACCUCAAGAGAUGAUGAAAAUUUUUGCCUUUGCCAACUCACUAGUGGAACUUCUGGCUGUGGGGUUAGAAACCUUUAAUAGAGCACGCUAUAGGCAGUUUGUGAAGCGAAUUGGUUAUAUGAUCAGGAUGACUCUUGGUUAUGUAAGUGACCAUUGGGCACAGUAUGUGAGCCAUAACCAAGGCUCAGGAUUGGCCCAACAGCCCUACUCUAUGGAGAAACUACAGGUUGAAUUUGAUGAACUGUUUUUGAGGGCUGUCCUACAUGUGCUGAAGGCCAAAAGACUUGGCAUUUGGCUGUUUAUGUCCGAGAUGCCCUUUGGGACUCUGUCUGUGCAAAUGCUGUGGAAGCUCUUCUACCUCAUGCACCAGGUGGAGAGCGAGAACCUGCAGCAGCUCUCCUCCUCCCUGCAGCCCGCCCAGUGCAAGCAGCAGCUCCAAGACCCAGAACAUUUUACCAACUUUGAGAAGUGUCUUUCUUCUAUGAAUAGCUCAGAAGAGAUUUGCCUUCUGACUACCUUUGCUCAGAUGGCUCAGGCCAGAAGAACCAAUGUGGACGAAGACUUCAUAAAAAUUAUUGUUCUGGAGAUAUAUGAGGUAUCUUAUGUCACCUUGUCUACCAGAGAGACUUUUUCAAAGGUUGGUCGAGAGCUUUUAGGGACUAUCACAGCUGUUCACCCUGAGAUAAUUUCCGUCCUUCUGGAUAGAGUUCAAGAGACCAUUGACCAGGUUGGAAUGGUUUCUCUAUACUUGUUUAAAGAACUGCCUUUGUAUCUUUGGCAACCUUCUGCAUCUGAGAUAGCGGUGAUUCGGGAUUGGUUAUUGAAUUACAACCUGACAGUGGUGAAGAAUAAACUGGCCUGUGUUAUUCUUGAAGGACUGAAUUGGGGAUUUGCUAAACAGGCUACCCUUCAUCUGGAUCAAGCAGUCCAUGCUGAAGUGGCUUUAAUGGUUCUUGAAGCUUAUCAGAAGUACCUUGCACAGAAGCCAUAUGCUGGGAUUCUCUCUGAAAGUAUGAAGCAGGUUUCAUAUUUGGCCAGUAUUGUUCGAUAUGGAGAGACACCCGAGACCUCAUUUAACCAAUGGGCCUGGAAUUUAAUCUUGAGGCUAAAACUGCACAAAAACGAUUAUGGAAUACAGCCGAAUUGUCCAGCUGUUCCCUUCUCCGUCACUGUGCCUGACAUGACAGAGUCACCCACGUUUCAUCCUCUCUUGAAGGCUGUGAAAGCGGGCAUGCCCAUUGGCUGUUAUCUAGCCUUAUCUAUGACAGCUGUGGGCCACAGCAUUGAGAAGUUCUGUGCAGAAGGCAUCCCACUAUUGGGAAUUCUGGUCCAGUCAAGACAUUUGAGAACAGUGGUUCAUGUCCUGGAUAAGAUUCUGCCUUUAUUUUACCCUUGCCAGUAUUACCUUCUGAAGAAUGAGCAGUUUUUAUCGCAUCUCCUCUUGUUCCUACACUUGGACAGCGGUGUCCCUCAGGGUGUCACACAACAGGUCACCCACAAGGUGGCACAGCACCUGACAGGAGCCAGCCAUGGGGACAACGUGAAGCUUCUCAACAGCAUGAUCCAGGCACACAUAUCUGUAAGCACUCAGCCCAAUGAAGUGGGCCCCGUUGCUGUGUUGGAGUUCUGGGUUCAGGCUCUCAUAAGCCAGCAUCUCUGGUACCGAGAACAACCUAUCCUCUUCCUCAUGGACCACUUGUGUAAAGCAGCUUUUCAGCUGAUGCAGGAAGACUGCAUACAGAAAUUACUCUACCAACAACAUAAGAAUGCCUUGGGUUACCACUGUGACCGGAGUCUGCUCUCAUCUUUGGUAAGCUGGAUUGUGGCAGGCAACAUCACUCCUUCCUUUGUGGAGGGCUUGGCCACGCCCACUCAGGUCUGGUUUGCCUGGACAGUGCUCAACAUGGAAUCCAUCUUUGAAGAGGACUCCCAGCUCCGGAGAGUUAUUGAAGGGGAAUUGGUGAUAAACUCUGCUUUCACCCCUGACCAAGCUCUGAAGAAAGCCCAGACCCAGCUGAAGCUCCCCAUCGUGCCAUCCCUCCAGAGGCUGCUGAUUUAUCGCUGGGCCCACCAGGCUCUGGUCACACCUUCUGAUCACCCCCUCCUGCCACUCAUUUGGCAGAAGUUCUUCCUUCUGUAUCUUCACCGUCCGGGACCACAGUAUGGGUAUGCUGCCCAGUAUUGUAGGUUUCUGUUACCCAUAGAUGGUUGUAUUGGAAGAAGGUUUUUUCAAAGUCCUGCUCAUAUCAAUUUGUUGAAAGAAAUGAAGAGACGUUUGACCGAGGUGGCUGACUUCCACCAUGCUGCAAGCAAGGCCCUCCGUGUUCCAGCAGAGGGCAGUGAAGGGCUGCCAGAGAGCCACUCUGGCACCCCUGGUUACCUGACUUCACCAGAACUGCACAAGGAGCUGGUGAGGCUCUUCAAUGUAUAUAUAUUAUGGCUAGAAGAUGAGAAUUUUCAAAAAGGAGAUACCUAUAUCCCUUCUCUACCAAAGCAUUAUGAUAUUCACAGGCUAGCAAAAGUGAUGCAGAAUCAGCAGGAUCUGUGGAUGGAGUAUUUGAACAUGGAGCGCAUCUAUCAUGAGUUUCAGGAGACUGUUGGUCUGUGGACACAGGCCAAGCUUGAGUCCCAUUCCACACCCUGCAGUUUGUCCGUGCAGCUGGACUUCACUGAUCCUUUGCUGGCUAAAGAAAGGGUUUUAAGUAACUUGCGGAAGCAUGAGGCUCCCCAGCCUCCCCUUGCUCUGCACCCGACGAAGCCUCCUGUGCCAGUUAUUUCCUCUGCUGUGCUAUUGAGUCAGAAGGACGCCACCCAGCUGGUGUGCACAGACCUGAAUCUGUUGCAACAGCAGGCCAGAACCGCAGCUCUUCGGGAAUCUCAGCAGGUUGCUCUGGAUGGUGAGCUGUUAGACACAAUGCCAAAGCAGUAUGUGAAUCGUGAAGAACAGACCACACUACAUUUGGAGUGCAGAGGCAGCAGCGGUAAGAAAUGCCAAGGAGCCGCAGUUGUCACGGUUCAGUUUGAAGGCAUGCAUAAGAAUGAAGCCAUAAGCCAACAGCUUCAUGUUUUACGGAAGGAAGUGAAGCAGUUGCAAGCAGAAGCUGCUAAACCACCAUCACUUAAUAUUGUGGAAGCUGCUGUACAUGCAGAAAACUUGAUCACGGCCUUAGUGAAUGCCUACAAGUUGCAGCCUACACCUGGGAUUCAGAAAGUUGGCAUUAGCCUUUUCUUUACUAUUGUGGAUUACGUCAGCGAUGAGACGCAGCGUCAUCCCCCAACAAGGCAGUUCUUUACUUCAUGUAUUGAGAUCUUGGGACAGGUAUUUAUCAGUGGCAUUAAAUCAGAGUGCAGAAAAGUACUUGAAACCAUUCUGAAGAACAGCAGGCUCUGCUCCCUGCUGUCUCCUUUCUUCACUCCCAAUGCUGCACCUGCAGAGUUCAUACAGCUGUAUGAGCAAGUGGUGAAGUUUCUAAGUGAGGACAACAGUGAUAUGAUUUUCAUGCUGCUAACCAAGUUCGAUCUUAAACAAUGGUUAAGCGCCACUAAACCUCCUCUGUCUGAUCGUACCAGGCUUCUGGAGUCCAUUCACUUGGCACUUACUGCCUGGGGCCUUGAACCAGAUGAGGAUAUUUUGAUGCCAUUUAAUCUUUUCUGUAAGCACUGGACUUAUCUUCUUCUCUACCAGUUUCCUGACCAGUACAGUGACAUUCUCAGGCUGCUUAUGCAAAGCUCCGCGGAGCAGCUUCUGAGCCCCGAGUGUUGGAAGGCCACUCUGAGAGCCCUGGGCUGCUGCGCCCCCAGCUGCCAGCAGGGGGCAGCGUCCACCGAGGGCGCCGUGCUUCCCAGCUCUUCUGAUGCUCUCUUGUCAGACAAGCAGGUAAUGGAGACUAUACAGUGGCUUUCAGACUUUUUUUAUAAGCUUCGGUUAUCCAAGAUGGACUUUAAAAGCUUUGGUUUAUUCUCAAAAUGGAGUCCUUAUAUGGCUGAUGUGAAGACAUUCUUGGGCUACCUUGUGAAAAGGCUGAUUGACUUAGAAAUGACCUGUUUGGCCCAAGACCCAACUGCCAGCAGGAAAACAGUGCUGAAAUCCCUACAUUCAGUAAUCAUUCAGCUCUUUAAGCCAUGGAUCCUGGUUUUAGAGGACAACGAAAGCAGCCAACAGCGGCAUUACCCCUGGCUAGAGAGUGAUACUGUGGUGGCCUCAAGCAUUGUGCAGCUGUUCACUGACUGUAUUGACUCACUGCAUGAGAGUUUUAAAGAUAAGCUGUUGCCAGGUGAUGCAGGAGCCCUUUGGUUGCACCUGAUGCAUUAUUGUGAAGCAUGUACAGCACCCAAAAUGCCAGAGUUCAUUCUGUACGCUUUCCAUAGCACGUACCGGAAACUGCCAUGGAAGGACCUGCACCCUGACCAGAUGCUCAUGGAGGCCUUCUUCAAAGUGGAACGAGGAAGCCCCAAGAGCUGUUUCUUAUUUUUGGGGUCUGUACUCUGUGAAGUCAACUGGGUUAGUGUGCUCUCUGAUGCCUGGAAUUCCAGUCCCCACCCAGAAACCCGCAGCAUGAUUGUCUGCCUCCUUUUCAUGAUGAUUUUAUUGGCAAAGGAAGUUCAACUGGUAGACCAAACAGAUUCACCUUUACUUAGUCUCCUUGGACAGACAAGCUCACUUUCAUGGCAUCUUGUGGAUAUUGUGUCGUACCAGAGUGUGCUAAGUUAUUUCAGCAGCCAUUACCCGCCGUCCAUCAUCCUGGCAAAAGAAUCUUAUGCUGAAUUAAUCAUGAAGCUCCUAAAAGUGUCUGCGGGCCUUUCUAUUCCUACUGACAGCCAGAAGCAUCUUGAUGCAGUUCCAAAAUGCCAAGCUUUUACUCAUCAGAUGGUUCAAUUCCUCAGCACCCUGGAACAAAAUGGAAAAAUCACCUUAGCAGUCCUAGAACAGGAAAUGUCUAAGCUCUUAGACGAUAUCAUUGUCUUUAACCCGCCCGACAUGGACAGCCAGACCCGCCACAUGGCCCUCAGCAGCCUCUUUAUGGAAGUCCUGAUGAUGAUGAACAACGCGACUAUUCCAACAGCAGAGUUCCUUCGGGGCAGUAUCCGGACCUGGAUUGGCCAAAAAAUGCAUGGGCUGGUGGUGCUGCCCCUUUUAACAGCAGCCUGCCAGAGCCUGGCGUCCGUCCGCCACAUGGCUGAGACUACAGAAGCCUGCAUCACUGCCUACUUCAAAGAAAGCCCUCUCAAUCAGAAUUCAGGAUGGGGACCCAUUCUGGUAUCCCUUCAGGUUCCCGAGCUCACCAUGGAAGAGUUCCUGCAGGAGUGCCUCACCUUGGGCAGUUACUUGACUCUUUACGUCUACUUGCUUCAGUGUUUAAACAGCGAACAGACUUUAAGGAAUGAAAUGAAAGUGCUGCUCAUCUUAAGCAAGUGGCUGGAACAGGUGUACCCAAGCUCCGUGGAGGAAGAGGCAAAGCUGUUUUUGUGGUGGCACCAAGUCCUUCAGCUCUCCCUCAUUCAGACAGAGCAGAAUGACUCCGUCCUGACAGAAUCUGUCAUUCGAAUUCUGCUCUUGGUUCAGAGCAGGCAGAACCUCGUGGCUGAGGAGAGACUCAGCUCUGGGAUCCUGGGGGCAAUUGGGUUUGGCCGGAAGUCGCCUUUGUCUAACAGGUUCCGAGUGGUUGCCCGAAGCAUGGCUGCCUUCCUUUCAGUUCAGGUUCCUAUGGAAGAUCAGAUCCGUUUGAGGCCUGGCUCUGAAUUACAUCUGACCCCCAAAGCUCAGCAGUCUCUUCCCCUUCUCUUCUCCUACUAUGAAGAAAGGAAUAAUCAAAAUUCUGGAGUCAAAGAAUGCUUUUCUUUCCUUCCUCUGAAGAGAGGCAUGGAAACAGUUUCUGCCAUGAUUUUGUGUCAUUUGUCAGAUGGAUUCGGGAGGAACCUAUGUACUUCAUGCUUGUUGGCUGAUUUAACAACCUUCUCACUUACUCUUGGCAGCACUUAGCAACUGGUUCCUCUAGAAUUCCUUUCCGUUAGACAGUUUCAUAUAACAUUAUCUCAUAACCUAGGAACAUACCCAACAGCAGAUUGAACAGAUUUCACCUUAGCAAGAUGAGGCUGGUGCCUGGGAUUUCCGGUUGCGCCCUAGAACGGAAGGAGUGGACAAUCUGGUGGGGAGGACCCCACAGGUGGGACUGGGGAGAACGAGGACAAGGCAGGCUUUAGAAAUCGGUGUGGCAGGUGAGGCGCCCAGCAACAAGAGCAGCCUGCCACAGCAGUGGCUCUUGGUAAGGCAAGGUUGGGAAAUGGCACAGAACAGAAACAGGGAAGGCUGGGUGUGGGAUGCUGCAAAGGCCACAGAGGCUUGGGCUGCUGGCCUCCUUCUGGUUGUGGUUAAGUUAAUCAAUGCCUGCCUUCCGGACUCCUGGCCUCAGUUCUGUAGGCCUCCUUCCCACAAGGCUCACAGUUGAAGUACACAGUGAUAAUGGGUGUGCUGUACCUCUGGCAGUCACAUUAUGUGCCUCUAUGGAGUUAACCCUCUCAUCUUCCGUGUCUUUUAGGCUCUGAAUGCUCUUGAAUCCAUGGCAUCAAGUAAGCAGUAUGUUGAAUACCAGGAUCAAAUAUUGCAAGCCACCCAAUUUAUAAGGCAUCCUGGCCAUUGCCUUCAAGAUGGGAAAAGCUUCUUGGCUCUUCUCGUUAACUGUCUGUAUCCAGAAGUGCAUUAUUUGGACCACAUACGAUAGUUAACACUGAGGCUCUUGAAAAACCCAUUGCUGUUUAUGUUUACAUUUAACUUUGCUGUUGCACAAGUAACUUUGCUCAAUUGCACUGUAGAGCUCAGUUUGGCCAAUGUGUAGUUGACUGAGAUGCAAGUUGGGAGGCGUUAGAUAUUAGAUAAUUUUGGGGUGUGUGUGUGUGUGUGUGUGUGUUUUCUUAGCUCUUAAGACCUUCUGGGGACUCUUUAAGUUUUUAUAUUUAUCCACAAGAGAAACUUACUAAGUUCCACUUGGGUGCAGAGCCACUCACAGUUGCCGAAUGUCCCAGUCAUCUCACAAGACCUCCAGAUGGAGUUCUUUGUAUGUUUCCACUUCUGUCUCUGUUUUAUGUAAAUGUUCCAGAUCUGACAACCUUGGAAGUCACUCAGUACCCUUACUUUUAAACCCCAUUUGUGUUCCUCCAAAGUAAAGAAGUCAAUUUUGAAAAAUUUCUGCAUUUCUCAAAUGUGGACAAAUACAAUAGUUUUAAAGUAUUGUUUUUCUCAGAAGGGAGAUAAAAAUGCCGAGUUAGUUAAAGUGGGUCAUGUGUAAAAUACGACCACUUGAUCGUGAUUAUAGUGGGCAGUAGAGAUGAUGACAAGUCAAUUUCCAUCCAGCCGUGUAUCCUCAUGGAGAAGCUGCCUGUCUGAAUCAGGAUGGCAAGCUGGCAGUCUGGGAGGAGCAUGUUUUGCACAGAUGUUUUGUUUGGUCCACUUGGUGAGGAGUGCAGACAGGGCUGCCUCUCUCUAGUCGGGAGAGUCUGUGCAUUCCCUCGGGCCCUGACCCUAGCCUCAUUCACAUCACUUGCCCCUGUCGACACCUAAGUUUGCACCCUUUGAUAGACACCAUGUUCGAUAUCUGAAAGGCUCAGUGUCAGGAGACAGAGACUGAGGGAGACUGAAGACCUGAUUCUCUGUUCCCUGCUUGUUUUUUAACUUCAAACUCAGAUGAAGCCAAUGGACCUGCUGAAACACUUGUCUGUGGAAACUGGGUCAGGUCGGGAGAUCUACUGAAAUUUGGCUUUUUUUCCAUAGCCACGUGCCUUCUGUUGUUGACAGUUCAUUCAUUACCAAAGCCUGUGUGUAACUUUGCCUUGUUCUGUGGCCAUCUUCUUGCUCAUGUUAUUUCUCCUGGGAAUGAGCAGUUUGACUUCUGUUCCCACGUUCCUCAUUCUAUCAGCUCUAGAUGGAUUUUGCCUGCAUAGCUGGCUUAAUAUGUCUUUGUGUAUGGGUAGUCUGUAGCCUGAGAAUAUUUACCUAAAAAUGUCUAAACAGCCACCAAGAAUGUUUAUAGGGGUAUAGGAAUAUAGUUAACAGAGUGCUAAUCUCUCCUCAAAUGUCCUUUUGGAAUGCUUCCCCCAAAAUUGGGAAGUUGGUAGGAGCUUUUCUUUACUUUGAAUUUCUUUACUUGGACAGAACGAUUCUGCCUUAAAGACACGCUUUGCAGCUCUGAUAAAGAACAUCCCUGUUUAGUCUCUUGAGUUUUACAGGCCACAAAAUGUCCGUCUCAGAGGGAUCUGUCUCAGCUUUUCUUAUUUUUGCUUCUCUCCGUUUUCAAAAUUAAUCAUCUUGUUCUCUGUAUAAGAAAAUUUGAGAAGCUGUGGACAAUUUAAUAGUCUGAUCUGGCAACAGCGAUUUUUGUUUGGAAAUAUUUUGUGUUUUCUUUGAGGAGGAUAUAAUUACUGAUAUCCUAGGAUGUGAAAUUUUUGAGUGACAGUAUGCACAUUUUAAAGAAAAUUAUGAUUAAUCUGUAUAAUGUUUUUUGGUCUGUAAAAAUUAUAAAAAAUAAAAUCAUUUAUCUUUGGUUGUAACUGUUUAAAAACCAAAUUAUAGGGAUAUCACACUAUCUUGUAAAGUGUUUCAGCUGUUAAAGUUGCUGUAGGUUUUUAUGCCUGAUGUCAUUUAAUUUAUUUGACAUUGAACUUCAUUAAUAAUCAGAGAUGGUCAGUGAAAGCGCUUCCUCUUUAACUCUUUCUUGCUUAACCUUGGAAGGUUGACUCAACUCCUAGGUGUCUAUGGGAAACUCUGGGCUAGGAACGUGCUAUAAAGACACUGAGCUAGUUCAGACAUGGCCAUGCUGCUGUAGCCUCCUGGGAAAGAAGGGCGGCAGAGAGACCAGCCCGCCUGUUGGCUUGCAGGGGUAAUGAGCCUUGGCUUGAAAAAAUUGUUGGCCUCCAGAGAGCACGGGGCUGUGGUUUCAGAAUCAGUGAUGGGUGCCGCACAUCAAGACGGGAAUCAAGCAAGACCAAGGCCCUGUGGACUGAGCAGCGUGGAGGGCGAACGGCUGCAGGCUCCAGACUUCACCACAGGGUGGCCAACAGUGGCAUCGGGACCAAAUAAAGAUGUCUAACAGCUUCCUGGGAGCAGGAGGAGGCAGGAUUCUGGUUGCCAUGAAAAACAUCUCUCUCCCUCUCCAUCACUCCCCAUGCUGCAGUGCACAGGUGGGUUGCAGAGGCAGGCUGCAUCCCGGAAUCAUGUUGUCCCACUGCCUAUUAAUAGAACAAGUGAAGGGCAGAAUGCUGGAACACACCAGACAUAGAGGGAGGGAGGUCCUGCCAGAUGUGUCUACACAACUGUCUACAUAGCAUGACAGUAGCAGUGGAUUCGGGACCCACCUGUACAUGUUUCCAAAGCUCCUUCCUGCACACUCGGGACCUCAGCUCCAAGGCGUGACUCAUUUCUCAGUCUCACCAUCCUUUGUUGGCUCAGACAUCGCAUGCCUCUGCCCCACUGGGGUUGUGUGCCUGCGUCUCUCACUUCUUUGAGGUUGGGGAAAGCCUAGUCCAGAAAAUGAAAACCCAUAGACCAGCCUAACUUCCUUUCAACCAAGUGACGGCCUCCUGGUUCCUCUCAGUUCAUCAUCAAAAUCAGUGUGUACAUGUCAUACAAGCCAAGAGUGUUCAUGUCCUCGUUCCUUUCAAAUGAAGGUGAUAUAUACUUUUUCACUGAGUUUUUAUUCCUGAAAUUCUUUCUUCUGGAGCAGGAAGCAAAUGUCCUGGAAUCGUAGACUUUUACAGUCAGAAGGGUCAUUCACGUUCAUCUAGUGCCCCUCUCACUCUGCAGGGAUCCUCCUGCCUCUCCUCUGCCCCUGUCCAGUGCCUGGUGGUCCAGCCUGUGAUGGGCAGGCCUAGGCUGCCAUCCGCAGGCUCUGUAGUUCUGCUUUCUAUUGAACCAAGAUGUUUCUACGUUGCCUAUUGGUCGUGGUUCUGUCCAGAGCAGUUCAGGCUGGGGCUGUUCACUUGCCCCUCCUUGAGGCAGACCUUUAGAUAUUUUCAGUUUUCAUCACAUGUCUAACACCACUUCCACCCCACCCCUCACCUCUUAGGCUAAAUCCAAGCUAAAUCCCCCAAUGUCUUUUUUUUUUUUUUUUUUUUGAGACGAGUCUCAUCUGUCACCCAGGCUGGAGUGCAAUGGCAUGGUCUCGGCUCACUGCAACCUCCGCCUCCUGGGUUCAAGCUAUUCUGCCUCAGCCUCCCAAGGAGCCAGGACUACAGGUGCAUGCCACCACGCCCGGCUAAUUUUUGUAUUUUUUAGUAGAGACAGGGUUUCACCCAGCCAUUGAGACAAGCUGGUUUCAAACUCCUGACCUUGUGGUCCGCCCGCCCCGGCCUCCCAGAGUGCUGGGAUUACAGGCGUGAGCCACCGCGCCCAUCUCCCCUGCAAUGUCUUUAGUUAGACCUUUUCCACCAUCAUGUCUAACUGGGCUACGGUUUGGGGAAAGUGUCCAAAUUAGUCCGUGUUAUCCUAAAAGGGGUGUGCCCCGGAUUAGCAGGGCCAGGGCUAGGGUGAGACAAAUGAGGCACCUGGGGCAUACAUUUAAGUUGGUGCUUGCUUGCAGGUGCCAAGAGAGUGCUUCCUUGGGUUUACCCCCGUGGUGCCUCCUUUACCUCAUUCUGGCCCCAGCCCUGGGGUUAGAGUCGCACCAGUGUGGUCCAAGUGGCAUAAUUAUCUCCCUAAAUGCUUGGGCAGCAUCAGCUUUCAGUAGCUGUGCCCCAUGGGAGGCACAUUAAGCUAGUGGCAAGUUGAGACUGCAGACCUCAGCUUAAUAUCAGUUGUUGCCCAAGACAGAUCUCACCCCACAUCUUCAUGACAGGCCUAACAACAAGGCACUUUGCCCUUAAUCCUCUACUACUGCCUGCUCUUCAUUUUGGGCCAACUGUACAGCUCAUUUUGAGAUAGUAGCUGAUCAUUUUUCUGAUCAGUUAACUUUGUCUUAUUAAGCAAAAUGGAGAAUAUAAUGUUGGGAAAUAAGUGUGUUGAUUAAAAGAAAGUAUCCCCUUCUACCAUCUUCCAUUUGUGUCUGGGUUGUGCUGGGUAAAGUUCUAGACUUACUAACGCAGACUUCAUUUUGGUCCGGUUUCCACAGCAUGCCUCGGGCAUCAGUGUCCAGGAGUAGCUGUAUUUGAGGUUUCCUUCACUCUGGUAGGUUCCUGAUUCCUGAUGAAAAUAACUUGAAAAAAAAAUAAUUAUACUACUGAUCCUCUUUUGGGAUAAUGAAAUUGCGAAGGAAUGUUGUUGAUUAUAACUUUUAUUUUUUAAUGUACAGAUGUACUGUCUCUCAUUGAGCACUGAUAGAAUUUAUUUUUCUUUCAAUAGUUUAAAAUCACUUAUGUGGAGACACAUACUUAAGUGUGUUCAACUCGUUUUCUUCCCACAUAUCUAGUGUGACCUUUAAAAACCACAACUUUAUUUUGGACAUUAAAUGUGCAAUAUUCACUACUUAUUCAUUGUUCCACAUUUUUCAUACUUGUACAAAGGGUAAGUUUUUAUAUAAUGGUGAGAAACAGGAAGAAAUGACAACUGGUUAAGUAAAAUUCUGCAAAUAAACUAGAUUCGAAUUUAAUUUA